AACCCGCUCUGUGGCGGGGCUUCCGGUCGGGAGGGUCCGCCCGCUCUCGCGUCCUUUGCUGGGUCCAGACACCGGUACGUCCGGGCGGGUUUUUAGUCUCCCAAGCGAGAGCGUCGCAUUCACCCGCGUGGGUCUGCGGGCGCCCCAGACCCCAGAGGACCCGGCCCCCAACGCUUACCUGUCCCCUCUCCUGUCCCUCCCCCAUUCCAGCCCCUUCUCUCCCCAGCCGUUGCCCCUCCCCGCACCCCGCCGCGUCCGCGCGCCUCUCUCCGCGCGCACCCCCAACCCGCCCCCUUUUCUCUGGGAACCGCUCCUUCCGCUCCGCCCGCCUGGAGUCCUUCUGGCCGGAUUCCGCGGCAUCCUUCCAUAGACCCUCGUUGUUGCUUCCUCCUUGUGGUUCCGUUGCAAACAUUUUUAAAGGGCUGGUUAUUCUUCCUGAAAUGAGUUUGGUGAUUAGAAAUCUGCAGCGAGUCAUCCCCAUCAGGAGAGCGCCACUUCGCAGUAAGAUCGAGAUUGUAAGGAGGAUUUUAGGAGUGCAGAAAUUUGACCUGGGGAUCAUCUGUGUUGACAACAAGAAUAUUCAGCACAUUAAUAGAAUCUACAGAGAUAGAAAUGUCCCAACCGAUGUGCUUUCUUUUCCAUUUCAUGAGCAUCUGAAAGCAGGUGAAUUUCCCCAGCCUGAUUUUCCAGAUGACUACAAUUUGGGAGACAUUUUCCUAGGAGUGGAGUAUAUCUUCCAUCAGUGUAAAGAAAAUGAAGAUUACAAUGACGUCCUGACUGUAAGCGGGGAUGCUGAAAUCAUAUAACCUGGCUCAUGGAACAUGGGCCUUGCAAAGGGGUCAAGAUCACAACCCUGCAUCCAUGUGUGUCCGUGGGUACCGUAAGGGCUACUGGGGGAAGAACCUGUAAGCAGGGUGUGAGGAGCACCCAGGCUGGGUAGGGACUGCAUGCCCCAUGCCACAGUUGAAGGAGGGAGAGAACACGCUGUGAAAACACAGAAGCUCCCAGAGAAGCCUUCUCAGCUUUUAUCUCUGGAGUAGAGCAGACUAUGUUGAGCUAACACAGACCUGCUGAAUCAGCUUCUUUCUGAGCUGCCAGAAGUACAGAAGUUGGAGCCUCCACCACCUUCCAGAUCUGUUUCUCCUCAGUGUAAUCCACCUAUGGGUUCUUCCUGCCCACUGCACAGACAAAACCAAUUCACUGCAAUUGUGGUAUUGCAGUAGAGAAAGAGUUUAACACAGAGCUAGCCAAGCAGAAAGGCUGGAGUUAUUAUUCAACUCAAUCUCCCAGAGAACUCAGAGGCUACAGUUUCUACAGGCAAUUUGGCAGGCAGGGGCUAGGGAAUGCCUGCUGCUGAUCGGCUGCAGACGGACCAUGGGGUGUCAACGAUUUUUGUCCCCUGAGUCCGCCUCUGCGUGGAGCCACGGGAUCAGCUGAGUCAUGAGUCUCAGGUCCAGGUGGAGUCUGUAGGUUGCCAGAACUCAAAAGUCUGAAAAACAUCCCAAAAGACCAUUCUUAGGUUGUACUAUUGACGUUAUCUUAUUGGGGAGCAAUUGGGGCGGUCACAAAUCUCGUGACCUCUGGCUGCGUGAGUCCUGAGCAGUAGGGAAUUACAGCAGGGCAAGCUGGGGAAGCAAGGCCUGCGGGCUGGUUCUCCUCAGGACACCUACAUCUGAGCAGAAUUCAGGCCCCUCCCAUCAUCCUAAUCUUGUGGCCCUUCACAAGCUUCACAGAGGUGGCUUCGGUCUUGAGCAAGGAGGGGAUUCGUUUUAGGGAGGGAUGAUUACUAUUCUUGAUUUAAAGUUAAACUCUAGAUUAAAUUCCUCCCGUGGUUA